GGGACUUUUUGGACACCCAGAGAACAGGUCCCAGAUACCGAGUCCGCAACUCCAAACAUCGCGAUUAAUAGGAGGUGAACACAGCUUUUCUCUUCUCUUUGGGAUGCUUUGUUGUCUGGUGGUGACUGUGCCCAUGGGUGAGUUGUAUCGGAAAAUCGUCAUGUGAGGAUCAGAGGGGAAAAGAAAACAGAGGCCUCUGGUCUCUGCCUGCCCUGGGUGCUCAUGGAACCAGCUGCUGCUCUGCACUUCUCCCUGCCAGCCUCCCUCCUCCUCCUCCUGCUCCUCCUCCUUCUCAGCCUGUGUGCACUGGUCUCAGCCCAGUUUACUGUCGUGGGGCCAGCUAAUCCCAUCCUGGCCAUGGUGGGAGAAAACACUACAUUACGCUGCCAUCUGUCACCCGAGAAAAAUGCUGAGGACAUGGAGGUGCGGUGGUUCCGGUCUCAGUUCUCCCCCGCAGUGUUUGUGUAUAAGGGUGGGAGAGAGAGAACAGAGGAGCAGAUGGAGGAGUACCGGGGAAGAAUCACCUUUGUGAGCAAAGACAUCAACAGGGGCAGCGUGGCCCUGGUCAUACAUAACGUCACAGCCCAGGAGAAUGGGAUCUACCGCUGUUACUUCCAAGAAGGCAGGUCCUACGAUGAGGCCAUCCUACGCCUCGUGGUGGCAGCUGUGAUCAUCAGAGACAAGUAUGUGAGGAAUGUGUCCUGCUCUGUCAACAACACCCUGCUCGGCCAGGAGAAGGAAACUGUCAUUUUUAUUCCAGAAUCCUUUAUGCCCAGCGCAUCUCCCUGGAUGGUGGCCCUAGCUGUCAUCCUGACCGCAUCUCCCUGGAUGGUGUCCAUGACUGUCAUCCUGGCUGUUUUCAUCAUCUUCAUGGCUGUCAGCAUCUGUUGCAUCAAGAAACUUCAAAGGGAAAAAAAGAUUCUGUCAGGGGAAAAGAAAGUUGAACAAGAGGAAAAAGAAAUUGCACGUAAGGAAUUUGUAAAGAAAGUGUGGAAAAAUAGAAAGAAAUUCAAAAAGAAAAGUUAAAUGAGUAGGAGGACAAUUGACUGUCAUAGAAAGGCCACAGCUCUCACAGGUACCGGCUUAGGGAAGAGAGAGAGGAAAUGCACAGCAGCAGCCACAAGGGCUUGGAACUCUCAUGUCAUAAGAAGUAAUCAUUCAGAGCUUUCUUUCUUCCAUGCUGCACACAUUACAUUCAUUCACCUGGCUAUAUGCAGCACUACAUGGCUGAACGAAAGUUCAGACAAAAGUCUAACAAUGUACUGAUACUACCCAGCCAUCUGAUCAUACAUCAUUGCUGGUUUCUGACUGUUCCUUAGGCAUAAACGAAGGGUGAUGUUGGUGUUCAUAGAAAGGAUGGUUCCUACGUUGUUUAAUACAAGCUCAAUUUCUCUUAGUUCUUCUGUUGAAGACAUGAUUUUGUUUCUGUAUUUUGUUUUCAGAGCAACUUCAAGAAGAAUUGCGUAAGUUUAGCCUUUCCUGAACUACUCCGUGUACAAUUUGUGUUCUGCUUACUUAGCAGUGUCUCGUGACAUUCACCUCUGUCUGUCCCUUGCAGGAUGGAGAAGAACAUUCUUACAUGCUGGUGAGUGCCUCUGAUGUUCUCUCAGAUCUCAGCUUUCUCCCCACUAGCCAGCUAACAGGACUCCUUAGAGGAGAUGAGCAAGGGGCCCAGGGCUACACAGGGACCAUAGGGAACUGGGGUCAGUUCAUCAACGGUGUCCCAGCAAUGAUGCAUCAUGGCUCUUCUGUCAGGGAACCCCAGCAGCUCUUAAUGAACCCUGCAGUUUACAUCCCCAGGACCCUUUCUCUUUUGGAAUAAUUUAAUGCAUGAUUAUCAAAGGUUUCCCAUGCAUAGUAGCCUCCUAAGAGUUACAUUUCAGAAGUCAUUGCUCUUUGAUUCUGGAUCAAUUUGAAAUAAGAUAAUGCUGUCUUAGCAAUUCAUAUCCUGGGAAUGGUAUAGACUGUGCACAGUUGAAGACCUAUGUGAGGAAAAGGCCAUAAGGGUCCCCAGUAAGCCUGAUGCAAUGGUGUACAAAUAGGUGGCCAGAAAUACCUUUCUGCCUCUAAGAGAGCACUGAUAUUCUGCAUGUAGUCUGCCAGGGGAAGGGGUUUGGGUGAGUGGGAGGGUGAGUGGGAGAGCACAGAGAAACCAAUCGCCCACUUCCAGUGAGUUCUCAUCUUGUGAUUCGGCACCUCUGCCUGUCAGCACCAAAGAAUCCAAACUUUACCAGAUACCAGGGCCCAUGGACCUUUCCUCUUUGGCGAGUUUCAAAAUUGCCACUGUCAUUUUGGGACACAAUCACAACUUGUCACAAUCAGACAUAUCAACUUGUGGAAAAGAGAAAAUCAUUUUAAUGCAAUAGAAAGGUAGACUGAAUAAGUAAGAAUACAUGCAGAAGGUAGAGGUUUGCAGAAUGCUCAGCUCCUGGGGCUUUUCCUGUAUGGGAGAAGUAAUCCUGGUAGAUGUCAGACUCAUAUUGUUAAAGCAAAACUGGAUUGAAGUAUUUCUUCCCUAACUUUGCCCACACAUCCCUCAGGCACCAGGUUUUCUUUUGCACACAUUUAUUCUCCUUCUUUAUCCUUUGAAGUGUGCCCUUGUCAGCCACUUAAAUCAGUUGUCACCUAUUAAAACAACCUAUAGGACCAACGAAGAGGUCCUUCACCACCUAGGACAGUGUGUAAUGAUAGACUCACUUAAUUGAUCCAUUGAGAGGUAUGUGGGGGAACAAUAGGAGAUAAAGCUUCUGUGAUGGUUUAAGCCAAGUUGGAAAGUUUCUAACUAAAGAAAGUCCCAGAGAUCAUAUAUCUUGAAUAGAAAAGGGAUCAGAUCUUAGAAUGCUGAGAAAAACUGGGAACCAUUAAUUUUGGCUCAUUUCCUAAACUCUCUGGAUUUCAUAGAGCCACAAUUCUUCUCAACCUGGGGGCACUGCUUCUGUCUCUGGAGAGAUAGAAGUGCAGCUUCCGUAAUUCUCAGGGUAUGAGCUGCCUGGGAUCAGGGGACCUUCAUGGAAACGGCCACUACAUGGGGAACCCCCUUCAGCUUUCUGAGACUUCUCUGGGGACCAGGAACCACACAAUCCCCAGGGUUCCUGAGACCCCAGGCAUAAACCUGAGACUUCCUCUGCAGCUGAUGUGGUCCUGGAUCCAGACACCGCUCAUCCCGAGCUCUUCCUGUCAGAGGACCGGAGAAGUGUGAGGCGGGGCCCCUACAGGCAGAGAGUGCCUGACAACCCAGAGAGAUUCGACAGUCAGCCUUGUGUCCUGGGAUGGGAGAGCUUCGCCUCAGGGAAACAUUACUGGGAGGUGGAGGUGGAAAACGUGAUGGUGUGGACUGUGGGGGUCUGCAGACACAGUGUUGAGAGGAAAGGGGAGGUCCUGCUGAUUCCUCAGAAUGGCUUCUGGACCCUGGAGAUGUUUGGAAACCAAUACCGGGCCCUGUCCUCCCCUGAGAGGAUUCUCCCUUUGAAGGAGUCCCUUUGCCGGGUGGGCGUCUUCCUGGACUAUGAAGCUGGAGAUGUCUCCUUCUACAACAUGAGGGACAGAUCGCACAUCUACACAUGUCCCCGUUCAGCCUUUACUGUGCCUGUGAGGCCCUUCUUCAGGUUAGGGUCUGAUGACAGCCCCAUCUUCAUCUGCCCUGCACUCACAGGAGCCAGUGGGGUCAUGGUGCCUGAAGAGGGCCUGAAACUUCACAGAGUGGGGACCCACCAGAGCCUAUAGAAUCAAUUCCUUGGACUCACAGCCAUGCAGAUAAGCCCUGGCCAUCUCAGCAGCCACCGCACAACCCCCCUAAUGAAAGACACGCCCUCCUCCCCUCUGGUCACGUAAGAGAACAUCUUCCAGCUGCCUUUUUCACACCCACUCCAGCCCUCUGCCCCAGUUUUCUCCUCCUCACUAGUCUGUGGCUUUAGUAGUUCCUUUGCUUGUAAUUAUGGGAUGGGAUCCAGGCAUAGGGAACUAGUUGUUUCAUAGCUCCCAGUCAAAAAGAAAGUGAGAGAAGCUGUUGGGCAGCGAACCUACUGUUUAAAAUCAGGAUAACCACAUUAAGCCCAAUAUGCCAGUUGGCACCAGAUGCUGUGGACUUGGAAUGAGGCCAACAGGGUUCACCAGGAUGAGAGAGGAGAGAGGAAUCCACAGGACCACCAGAAGGGAGAGGGAACCAGAUAUGCAGAUCAGAGAUAGAGGAAGUGGAACCAGAGAGCUGGGAGGGACCAAGGUUGUAAGGAUGGCUAAGUCCCACCAUAAGAGCUAAAGGGUCCUGGGAGAUGAUGGCUCAUUUCCACCCAACCCCAGGAUUUCCACAGCACACACCCACAGGCCUGGACCUGGGAUGAAGAUGAAUGAAGAACAUGGACUCAUGUGGAUGUGGUUUGGCUCAGAUGUCCCUGCAAUAAACAAGGGGUCAGUACUUAGUCCCUGAGUGUGGUUGAGGUUUGAGGUCCUGGUCGAGCAGGGCAGUACUGGACCAGGUCUACGUCAGCAUUCAGGUUCAAUGGGGACACCAGUGGCUUCAAACUUCCUGAUCUAAUUAUGUUUUUAGACACUUAGAAGUUAUUGAGGACUUUAAAGAGCUUUUGUUUAUUUGGGUUAAUAUUUAUGACAUUUGACAUUGAAACAAAAAUUUAAAAUGUUAUCUUUUAAUUUAUGUUAAAAUAGCAUUAAUAAAUCAGUUAUAGGUUAAUGUAGAUAGGAUGUUUUGUGAAAAAGCAAUCUAUUGUGUCCAAAUAAAAAAACAAAAAGUGUGACACUGGUUAACUUUUUCCAGAUCUCAUGUCUGGCUUAAUAAGAGAUAUUUGUAUUAUCAUAUCUGCCUUUGUAUUAAACCUAUUGGUAUAUCAUAGGUCAUGUUAGCUCAAAAAAACUUUACUGCACACUACUGAGAGAAUGAGAUGAAAAACGAUUAAUGUUUCAUUAUUAUUAUUGUGAAAAUAUUAUUAACACUGGGGACUCCUUAAGAGUACAUCAGAGUUCUCUCUAGGAAUCCCAAAACCACAUUUUGAAACUAGAAUAGUGGAUCCUGGAAGUUAAUCCAUGUGCUGGUUAAUUUUAGAUGUCAACCUGACUGGAUUAAGGAAUACCUAGACAGCUGGUACAACAUUAUUUCUGGGUGUGUCUGUGAGUGUGUUUCCAGAAGAGAUUGGCAAGUGAGUCAGUGGGAAAUUCUCUCCUUCUGUUGGCUGGGUGCCCAAUACAACAAAAAGGCAGAGGAAAGGCAAAUUCUUCUCUCCUCUGGAGCUGAGACACUCUUCUUCUUCUGCCCUUGGACAUCAGAACUCCUGGCUCUCCGGCCUUUGAACUUCAGGACUUGUACCAGGAGGCCCUGGGUUCUCAGGCCUUUGGCUUUGGACUGAGAGUUACACAAUCAGCUUCCCUGGUUCUGAGGCUUUCAGACUUAAACUGAGCCAUGCUACCAGCAUCCCAGGGUCUCCAGCCUACAGAUGAGCUGUUGUGCGAUUUCUUAGCCUCCAUAAUCACAUGAGCCAAUCUCCUUAAUAAAUGCCUGCUCAUAGAUCUGUAUCUACAUCUAUAUCUGUAUGUGCAUCUAUAUCUAUGCCUAUAUCUAUAUCUAUAUCAUAUUGAUUUUGUCUCUCUGGAGAACCCUGACUAAUAAAAUGAGGCAUCUAAAA